AGACAGUUUCGACACUUUGCAAAGACAAAGAGCCCUAGACCGGAGGGAGGAGGAGGAGGAAGAAGAGCGGAGAGAGAAGGAAGAGGCGAUGUGAGCUGGGAAGGGGGCAAGUGUCCGGGACACCCACACCCCUGUAUUCUCCUCCGAACCCCUUCAUGCCCAAAUCCCGGAAACUCCAGCGUGUCUCCAGCCGUGUUGGUACCAUUUUCAGAUUUCAUCUUCCUAAACUGGAAAUGUCAAUGAGAGGAAAUUAACACCCCCAAGAGCUGCAGUGAGCAAAUGCAUUGAGCUUGGGUCAGGACAAUUCCAUUUGGGGACCAGAGAUGGACGGUCACUCAGCCUAUGGAGGCAGACCCAGAAGGCACUGCAGGACUUCAGAGAGCAAAGAGGGAAGUCAAGGAACCUUAUCCUGUGGUUUCCUCUACUGAUGAGUGGUGGAGUUGAGAAUGUCCAUCUUUCCCCAACAGCAUGGUAGCACACUCAUUUCUCUUCCCUACUGUCACCUGGCAUCUGAUUCAAACACCAAAUUACUUGGACUCCAGAGUCUAGAACACGUUUCUUAUGUGGAAUUCUUGGAUUUCUGUCUUUCCUUCCUGCUGCCUAUAAUCUUCUGAGGCUCCCAAAUGUCUCUGGGUCAAGGACUAACUUGUAGGCCUGGGUUUUGAGGUCCCUCUGCAGUUUGCCAAGUUUCUUUAUUUUUAUUUUUAUUUAUUAUUUAUUUAUUUAUUUAUAUAUUUAUUUUUUAGUAGAGACAGGGUUUCACCGUGUUCGCCAGGAUGGUCUCCAUCUCCUGACCUUGUGAUCCACCCACCUCGGCCUCCCAAAGUGUUGGGAUUGUAGGCGUGAGCCACCACACCCAGCCCAGCUUUUUUUUUCUUUUUUUUGGGACAAAGUCUCACUCUUGUCCCCCAAGCUGGAGUGCAAUGGCACGAUCUCGGCUUACUGCAACCUCCGCCUCCCAGAUUCAAGCAAUUCUCCUGCCUCAGCCUCCUGAGUAGCUGGGAUUACAGGUGCGUACCACCACGCCCGGCUAAUUUUUGUAUUUUAAGUAGAAACGGGGUUUCACCAUGUUGGCCAGGCUGGUCUCGAACUCCUGACCUCUGGUGAUCUGCCCACCUCUGCCUCCCAAAGUGUUGGGAUUACAGGCGUGAGCCACCGUGCCCAGCCGCAGUUUGCCAAGUUUCUUCCAACCAAUCCUAUCUUUCAAGGUUGCCCAUCACCAUCUCCCACUGUAAUACAAAGGAGAUCUGCCAUUUAUUUGCUUAAUACCUAAAAAUAUUUGCUCUUAUUUAGGGAGCCCUUGCCACAUGCCCAAGCUGGGCAGAUCGCUUUGUACGUGUUGUCUUGUGUGAGCCUCACAAGGACCCCAUCAGGUCAGUCCUGUUGUUCUCAUCUUACAGAUGAAAAAUUGGAACUCAGUGAGGUAUAAUAACCUAUUCAAAGUCUCAAAGCCAGUGAGGAAUAGAACAAGGGUUAAUGCAAGUCAGUCUGGCCCAGAACCUGUGCUCUCUACUUCUCGGUCAGCACUCUCCAAUAGAACUUUCCUGAUGAUGGAAAUGCUCUAUGUCGGUACUGCCCAGGUCAGUAGCUGCUAGCCACAUGAGACUGUUAAGCACUUGAAAUUGAGCUGGUGCAACGGAGGAACUGUUCUUUAAAUUUUAUUCUAUUUUAAUUCAGUUAAUUUAAUUAGUGGCAUUAAUUAGUUAAUUAAUGAGUGCAACUGAGGACUUGUAUUUUAAAUUUAAAAUAUAAGUUUAAUUAGAAAUAGCAGGUGAGUGCAGUGGCUCACGCCUGUAAUUCCAGCACUUUGGGAGGCCGAGGUGGGUGGAUUGUGGGGUCAGGAGUUCGAGACUAGCCUGGCCAAUAUAGUGAAACCCUGUCUCCACUAAAAAUACAAAAAUUAGCCAGGCAUGGUGGCACACACCUGUAAUCCCAGCUACUCAGGAGACUGAGGCAGGAGACUCGCUUGAACCCAGGAGGUGGAGAUUGCAGUGAGCCAAGAUUGCACCACCGCACUCCACCCUGGGCGACAAGAGUGAAACUUCGUCUCAAAAAAAAAAAGAAAAGAAAAGAAAGAAAAGAAAUAGCCACGUGAGGCUAGUAGAUAUAAAGAACUGUGACAGACCUGAGAUGUCAACCUAUUUGCAAGCCAACAAAUUAGCUCGUUGGCAGAUGCUGACAAAAGAUAGCAGCUUCCUGGAUCAGAGCCAAAAGACUUUACUCCAGCACGGCAGGCAGCCUUAAGUUUCAUGUUUACAUCAUUUCUACUUGUACCCCAAGACCCACGGGCUUGCUUCAUAGAUGAGGAACCACAAUCUUUUAUUAUAAUGGGCUGCAAGUGAACCUACUCAACUUCUCUCUUGGAGGGAGGCAUUAUCUUUAUGAUACUGGAGAGUAAGCACACCUGAGCCCUGCUCUGGAAGGAGACACUAUCUCUAUGUUCCAGGCUCUGUGCCUCCUUAAAAAGGUAGUUCAGAAAAGAAGGCUGUCAGUGCUUCUGCUUGCAAGACACACAGAAGUGCAAGAGACCCAUGAAGAAUUGUCUGUCAACCAUGGAUCCUGCAUUGGAUACUGCAACUCCAAAUUGUCUGCAGUGCCUGUUCUGGGAUGUUUCACAUGUACUACAUCAUUGACCACCCCCAGGUGUCUGCAGAGUUAGCCCGUCUUUUCUGUUUAGCAGAUGAAGAAACUGAGGCUCACUCUCACCCAACUUCCUGAACUUCGAGAUCGUGGAUUCUCCUCCCCAUUACCAACUCUUUCUACUUCCCCCUAGAUCCCCCGAAAAAACAAAAAUCUGGAAUGUUUGUCCUCCUCACUCCUUUUCAAAACUUUACCCUCCAAGACUAGAAUUCCUUUUCUCUUCUGCCUUGUCAUCUUCUUCCCAUUUUCCAGAAGAGUUGCCAGUCUGACCUCCUCUCCGAAGCCUUCCCUGCCCAGCCCAACCUAUGCUGAAUUCCCCUGUCUCUUCUCGACCAUAGAAGGUCCUAUCUCAUACUCUUGAGUGGAAGCUCUUGAGGGCAGAGCCUGUACCUUCCUGUGGCCACUCUCCCCCAGCAUGGCCUAUCUCAGGACUUGGGGGAAAAACAAACUAACAAAUAAGGACUCAAAAAACCAAACCAGAAACAAGCAGCUAUUAUUUUAUGCCUGGGAUUGACUUCCCACUUCACUACCCACUUUCAGUUCCAGGCCCCAGGCAGUGGGUGAAUGGGCUUGAUUCUUUCCCAGAAACGGGAGAUGUUUUGAAAUGACUCAAAGAAAAGCUGAUUGGAUUGGAUUGAGUUUUGGUAAAUCCACCCACAAGAGCAGAGAAACUUGACAUUUGCCUUCCAAGCCAGCAAAAGGGAUGAAUCUCAUUUCCUUCUAACUGAGCAGGAGGCCCAGCGAUGGAAUGAUGACUGAGCAGGUCUCAGGAGACUGGGUUCUAGUCCAAGUUCUGAGGCUGGCUGGCUCCAUGACCUUGGGGAAGGCACUGCCCUUUUCCAGGCCUUAGUUUCUCAUCUAUGAUGCAGGACUGGAGGAGGGGGAGAGGAGUCAGACUCUCCAGAUGCCCUCCCUCCCCACCUUCCAUGCUGGGCUUCAGUGAUCCUCCAGGCUGGGAAAGCCCAGCCUUCACAGGAACCCAGUGAAGUUCUGCUCCUCCCAGCCUCCUUUCUGCCACCUCCCUGAGCAGGACCAGCCUCCCCUCCUCUCCAUGUACAGUGUAGACAUCCCACACUGCCUGGCUGAGGGAGCACCUACUGUAAGGCUGUGCUGAAAGAGCAGCACUUGAUUCUAAUCCAGACUCCUCUAUCUUCAGCCCUAAUGCAUCACCUCAUCGUAAACAUAAUUCACAGUGCUGCCAUCUCUGCCUUUCAAGAUGAAGAAACUGAGGUUCAGAGAGGUUAAGAGACUCCACUGAGGUCACACAGCCGAUGACAGACAACCUUCUGUGCCUUCAUCAAGCUGGUUGUGUACCCACCAUGUCCCUGGCGACAGGAUGGGAAAGAAAAAGCCCUAAUUAAGGAUCGUCAGAAACCACAGUUGGAGGAGGACGGCAGAGACAGUUUCCCUCCCCGCUAUACCAACACCCUUCCUUCGAGGUCCUCGCUCCUGAGGGACCCUGGACUGUCACAGAGAUUAAUGACCCCUUAUCUUCUUUGGAUGUGAAAGGAAAUCACUGGUUAAAGCUUGAUCGAGAGACAUUAUCAGCUCUUUAAGGAUUGCAGAAGAAUAGGCUACUUUAUUUUCUGAAAAGGUAAAUAUAUGCAAGCAAAGCCAACAUGCCACGAAUGGCGUUGGUCUACCACACAGCCGUGUCUGGGACACAGUUGGGGGUCAUCCCCCAGCAGGAGUGAAGUCGAGCUUAGCGGCCCUUGUGUCCUCCCUUGGAAUUCCUGCCAUCCCUUUUGAUUGAGCCUCCACCUCUGGGAUUUUUCUUCCAUUUUUCUCCUCUCUUAGGAGGGAGUUCCUGCUACCCAUCGUGGGAGGCCACCAUCAGGACUGCGAAGAUGGUGACCCUGCGGAAGAGGACCCUGAAAGUGCUCACCUUCCUCGUGCUCUUCAUCUUCCUCACCUCCUUCUUCCUGAACUACUCCCACACCAUGGUGGCCACCACCUGGUUCCCCAAGCAGAUGGUCCUGGAGCUCUCCGAGAACCUGAAGAGACUGAUCAAGCACAGGCCUUGCACCUGCACCCACUGCAUCGGGCAGCGCAAGCUCUCGGCCUGGUUCGAUGAGAGGUUCAACCAGACCAUGCAGCCGCUGCUGACCGCCCAGAACGCGCUCUUGGAGGACGACACCUACCGAUGGUGGCUGAGGCUCCAGCGGGAGAAGAAGCCCAAUAACUUGAAUGACACCAUCAAGGAGCUGUUCAGAGUGGUGCCUGGGAAUGUGGACCCUAUGCUGGAGAAGAGGUCGGUGGGCUGCCGGCGCUGCGCCGUUGUGGGCAACUCGGGCAACCUGAGGGAGUCUUCUUAUGGGCCUGAGAUAGACAGUCACGACUUUGUCCUCAGGAUGAACAAGGCGCCCACGGCAGGGUUUGAAGCUGAUGUUGGGACCAAGACCACCCACCAUCUGGUGUACCCUGAGAGCUUCCGGGAGCUGGGAGAUAAUGUCAGCAUGAUCCUGGUGCCCUUCAAGACCAUCGACUUGGAGUGGGUGGUGAGCGCCAUCACCACGGGCACCAUUUCCCACACCUACAUCCCGGUUCCUGCAAAGAUCAGAGUGAAACAGGAUAAGAUCCUGAUCUACCACCCAGCCUUCAUCAAGUAUGUCUUUGACAACUGGCUGCAAGGGCACGGGCGAUACCCAUCUACCGGCAUCCUCUCGGUCAUCUUCUCAAUGCAUGUCUGCGAUGAGGUGGACUUGUACGGCUUCGGGGCAGACAGCAAAGGGAACUGGCACCACUACUGGGAGAACAACCCAUCCGCGGGGGCUUUUCGCAAGACGGGGGUGCACGAUGCAGACUUUGAGUCUAACGUGACGGCCACCUUGGCCUCCAUCAAUAAAAUCCGGAUCUUCAAGGGGAGAUGACGCAGUGAAGGGCUGAGGAUGGACGCACUGUCACACCUCUGCAUUUCCAGCCCCAGCAUCUUGCUGGAGCCGUUCCAUCCCGGAGCUUGGAGGGGCAGCCUCAGGUGUGUGCCUGGGCACCGCUCACAGCCUCUUGCACCCAGCCGUUGGCAGCAUCUACUCAGCAAGGUCACUAAGCUCUGCCAGCGUGGCAGAGCAUGUCUUGGAACCUGUCUUGAGUGGGGACAACGUCCCCCCACUGCUGCCCUAGAGCUGGGGAGACGCUGGGAAAGGUUCAACCUCCACACACUAAAAUCAUUUUGGCUCCUGGGGCAAGCUUGGGGAAUGAAUGUGGAAGAUGCCUAUAUUCUGAGAGACAGGACAGUUUCCCAGGAAGAUGGGCAGAGACUUGAGUGGCGAUUACCUCCAGCACAGAGACGUGCCAGGCGGUGUUGGCGCUCGGGGCGAGAUGCUGCCCUUCUUUGCACGAAGCCUGGCCUCUUGCUUGGCGUGAUAACCCUGUCAUCUUCCCAAAGCUCAUUUAUGAGCCACCAGAGGCUCCUACCCCAAAGAUUUUCACAGAAACUUGAGGCCAGGUGCCGUGGCUCACACCUGUAAUCUGAACACUUUGGGAGGCCGAGGCGGGAGGAUCACUUGAGCCCAGGAGUUCAAGACCAGCCUGGGCAACAUAGUGAGACUCCUGUCUCUACAAAAAUAAAAGAUUUAAAAAAAUUAGCCAGGCACGGUGGCACACACUUGUAGCCCCAGCUACUAGGGAGGCUGAGGAGGGAGGAUCUCUUGUGCCUAGGAGUUCGAGGCUGCAGUGGGCUGUGAUCACACCACUGCACUCCAGCCUGGGCAACAGAGUGAGACCCUGUCUCUGAAAAAAAAAAAAAAAGAAAAGAAAAAAAACCCCAAACUUGGCACCGUGUUUCUGACUCCUGCAGAUGCCUCUUCCCAAGCAGUUGUUCCUUUGAGUAGUCAGUCUCAUGGUUCUAAUCGUGGCGAGAGCGGAUCUGACCACUUCCAUGUGCCUUUGUAUUUGGGAAAGAAAAGCAUGCAUUGGCUGAAAUGAAACAAAAGCCCUUACUUGGGAAAAGGGACCCCCACCAGCGGCCCUGCUUGCUCCGUAGCUGGGAACAUCUUUUCUGGUUUCCUGAGCCAGCACCUGAAUUGCAACGAAGCUCUGAGGAUACUCAACACCACCCAGCAGUGCGUCAGAAUGGAACGUACAUUCUCAUUCUCAGACUGUUCAAUAUGGUGCCCGUAACCUCCAAAGCCACACAGGAGGCUGCCAGCAGCAUUUUCCCCAAGGGCCUGAGCUCAGGGUCAAGUCCCUGCUGGCCAUCUUGGGGCUGUCACUGGGGGUCUGGGUCAAGGACAUCCCAGGAAUGGUAACUGCCACAUACCUCAUCUUCUUACUCCCCAGCUACUCUCUUUUCCUCAUUAGCCUUCCUGAUUAUUUAUUGAUUUCUUUUUUUUAUUCAACUGACAUUGUUUGCACCCUGGCUCUGUUGGUGGUCCUGGUGUUUUAAUGAAGCUUGCCUCACCCAGUAGCUGGGAAAUUAGGUGGGGGUGCUUAAGGGAGGUUUGUAGGAGUCCUCGGACGUGGGAUAUUGGGGGUAUCUAGGGCUUGGAUGGUUUGUGGAAUGUCCUCAGCAUCCUCCCGUCCCAACCCAACCUUCCUUCUUCCUCAUUGUGGACUUGGAUUUAUUCUCAGGCUAGGAGUCUCCAAAACUCCGUGAAACCUUAUUGCUGCUGGGUGUGGAGUGGAGAGUGACAGGAAUGUGGGGGACGGUGAUUGUUGGCUCCAGUUACUAAUGUUUAAGCAGAAAAACCACUUUCUUGUUGAAAAUAUCCCUGAAAAGGUCGCUGCUGCUUUGAGGAGGCGUGACUUUUUCCUGGUGGAGUGUGACGGAGGCAUGGGGCCUGUGCUCCCAGGCUCGGGGGAGCCCCCUCUGCACACGGGGAGGGAGGAACUUGGGGACAUCAGUCAUGGGUCACAGGUGGCUUCAGGCCAUUCACAAGAGUCCCCGGAAGUUGCGUGCCAAGUUUGGUUUUUUCCCUGAAUCUCUGCAUAUGAGCAUUUUUCUGGAGAAAGGACCAUAGCUUUUAUUAGAUUCUCAAAGGUUCAGAAUGGGGAAUGUGUUAAACAAACCGAAAACCUGUUUCAGCUUUAAAAUCCUCCAAAACUUUAAAGACUUUUCUUUUUUCUGAGAAAGGCUGGUAAAUCACUGAGUCAUCAUUCAGAACAUACAGCCUCGAAGGGCAGAGCUCACACCCAUAUAUGACGUUAAGAGCUCAACAAAUGUUUGUUGAGUGACUGAGUGACCCCAGGGGCAGACUCCAGAUCAUCAGACACUGAUACAGAGAGCGAUGCUAUCUCCUCAACUCUCCCUCUUCUCCUAAAAGCUGAGUCUAUAUAGGGAUGACAGGCUCAGGCUGAGCAGUCGACUUCUCUGGGUUUUGCUGUGUAAGAAUAGGUCCCUCAACAUGAAGAUGUGUCUGCGUCUGAGCCAGAUGCUGCCUGGGUCGGUUGCCUGGCCUCCGUCUGGUCUCCCUCCCUCCUACUAGGGUGGUCAAGCUGUGAGAUCUCUUCCAGCCUCCAAAUCCAGCUUUCCCAUUUUACUGAUGAGAAAAUCAAGGCCACAUUGCAGCUGGGUGGGGAGUGGAGCGUGACAGGCACGGGAGAGGACAGCGAUUGUUGACUCUAGUUCCUGAUGUUUAAUCAGAAAAACCACUUUUCCUGUAGAGCACAUUUCCUAAAAGGCUGCUGCUGUGUAGGGAGGUGUGGCCUUUUCCUGGUGCAGUGUGAAGGAGGGAAGUGACGGGCAGUCGUGAACUGUCUGGGACAGAUAGCACAAGUCAGAGUUUGAGCAAAACUAGGGUGUUACCGGCGCUAUGUUGAAAUUGUCUGGAGGCGGGCUUUCCCAGCGAGUCUCCAUUCAGCAUCUGGAAAAAGUGUAACCAGAAUGGAGGUGUCUGACUCUCCUGUGCUCUCUCAGCGCCGAGCUCUAGCUGCAGGCUGCCUGGGUGGCCUUCUCACACCCUCCCGUGCAGGAGACUGCAUUUCUCUUUCCCACAGCCCAGCAGAUAGCUCAUUGGCUUAGCAAUGGGCACUUAACAGAAUCCAGUUGUUGCAGCCAGAAUUAAAUGCACCAGUCUGGCUUAAACCAACUGGAACUCAUCCCUGGGGUGAAGGUGGCUGGGAAUUAGACAAGAGUGUGUGUUAGCCAAAAGGCACAUGCAUGCUGUCAGCAGGAGAAUGAGGAGCACUGGUUCUGGGCAGGCAGUGGCAGGGGCUCCCUCAGGCCCCUGAUUCCCAGCCCACAGCUCUUUCUACUCUGCAGACAGAGUUCCUUGGAGACUGGCCCUGCAUUCAGGCAGGGAGCAGAGGGGUCCCUGCCUGCAGCACCCAGAGCUGAACCUGAAGCUACAAAGAUGGGCUGAUGAGGUGGCCCAUGAGGUGUCAGCAACAUCCCAACCCCCUGGGUCUCCCCAGUGAGUCAGGGCACUGAUUUGCUAUAGCUGGAGCUACAUGCACCUCUCCUCCCCUCAGCCACCUUUUAGGGGAGAAAGGAGGGCAGAUUUGUAACCUCUGGUUCUCUGCAGGGAUCCUGGGCUGGAAGAAAGUUCAUAAAUGGAUGAAUGCCUUUUAAAACUCCAGCUUUUCCAAGCAUCAUUCACCAAAGCAUUUGGUUAGGCUUAGAGAGAAAAGCUGGAUAUGAGAAAAUAGAAUGUAAAAUAGGAGGGAAAAAAAAAAAGAAGGUGGAGAGGGCAGUUAAGAUCUGGGUGAUUCUUUAGGGAAACGGCUGGUUGAGAGGCUUUGAUGGAAUCCCAUUCUCUGCUGUGGCCAGAAGGUGGUGCUAGAGGCCAGUCCCACUUGGAUGUGACCCUGGCCUCUGCCAGGAUUCAAACCACAAAGAACAUUUGGAACUGGGAUGUUUGCUUUGAAGCAGCCCGAAAACAAGUGAAAGGAAACCAAGAUAACUCUCUCUCCCUCCGCUGGCAAGGAUCAAAAAUACCUUGUGCAGGGAAGCCCGAGCCUCGAGGGGCCACUGCCCAGCUAAAGAUGACUGGACACCAGCCAUGCACCAUCAGGAACCAGCACCUGUCCUCACCCCUGAGAAGAGCCCCGGGGGUAUCAUUAUAUCCAUCGCAGACAUCUGGUUUGCAGCAAAUGUGGCUACACGCCAUCAGGAUUAUCCUGCCCUGUGGACUGGGCUAGCUAGUUUUGAGAUAGAGUCAACCUCCCCAUUUUUGUUUGUCAUGAAAACACCAGCUCCUGCACCCCUGGGGUGCUACCUGACACCUGUGCAAAGAAAAGGAGGAAAACUUAGAAGAAAAGGCAGAGACAGGCAAGACAGCAUCUCACAGCUUGUCAGGAUCAGGGCAUUACCGACUAUUUUUUCUUACCAAAAGAGCACUGAAUUUCCUAGGGGAAGGUGAGCCACCUUUACACCUCCUGUCCUCCCUCCCAGCCCGUCAAGCGAUCCCAUCACCCAGCCUCAUCACUCAGCUUCUUCCUAGUACAAAACUGCCAUCGGUUGUACGUCCUGAGCUGUGGGACGUCAGCUUUAACCCUAGCCUGUCUCAGGGCCUCGCCCUCCAGCCCCCCGCCCCUUAGGGUGAUCGUGGGUUUCUUCCCUUCCUCCUGCACAAUCGCUUCCCUUCACUGAAUUCCCUUCAAAGCCAAAGUUUCUUGAGCACUUUUUCUUGUGUGCAGUCUUGUGUGUUUGGGUGUUGGUGUUUUUAAAUUUGCUUUCUAUUCCCCCCUGCCUCUCUCCAUGUCGUUACGCAGCUGAGCACUGGUUGGGAUGCAUUCGAAUGACUUCAGCAAGAUCCUGCUUUCCUCAGCCCCCGCUCUGUUUUAUUUAUUGUUUAAUAUUUCCAAUGAUCCAAAUCAAAGUGAAUAAACAAAGAGCUAUUUUAUUGUU